GCUCCUCGCCUGGCCGUGAUAUCAAUGGCGCAGGCUUCACUUCUGCUGUGGCGGUGACUGAGGCCUUUCUGGUGACCUCAGCCCAACACAGGCCGUCUCCGGAGCUUCCCGGUAGUGGCCCCGGAUUCCCACGGUCUUUGUCAUUGGCUGUCAGCUAGCAGGCCUGGCCGCUCCCGUGCGGAGAGACCAUCUCUUCAGGGCAAUGUCCAGGCCGAGCAGCGUCUCCCCGCGGCAGCCGGCUCCUGGCGGUGGCGGAGGCGGCGGCCCCUCGCCUUGUGGCCCUGGGGGCGGCGGCCGGGCCAAGGGGCUGAAGGACAUUCGCAUUGAUGAGGAGGUGAAGAUCGCAGUCAAUAUCGCGCUGGAGCGCUUCCGAUACGGGGACCAGAGAGAAAUGGAAUUUCCUUCUUCUUUGACCAGUACUGAAAGAGCCUUUAUUCAUCGACUCAGUCAGUCUCUUGGUUUGGUCUCUAAAAGUAAAGGAAAGGGAGCAAAUAGAUACCUAACUGUGAAGAAGAAAGAUGGAUCAGAAACAGCUCAUGCAAUGAUGACCUGUAAUUUGACUCAUAAUACAAAACAUGCUGUUAGGAGCCUAAUUCAAAGAUUUCCUGUCACCAAUAAAGAGCGUACAGAACUUCUGCCUAAAACAGAAAGAGGAAAUGUGUUUGCAGUUGAAGCUGAAAACCGGGAAAUGAGCAAGACAAGUGGGCGACUCAACAAUGGCAUACCUCAGAUUCCAGUGAAAAGAGGAGAAUCCGAAUUUGAUUCUUUUAGGCAGUCUUUACCAGUGUUUGAGAAACAGGAAGAAAUUGUUAAAAUAAUUAAGGAAAAUAAAGUAGUUUUGAUUGUAGGAGAAACUGGGUCUGGAAAGACCACACAGAUUCCUCAGUUCCUUUUAGAUGAUUGCUUUAAAAAUGGUAUCCCCUGCCGUAUAUUUUGUACUCAACCAAGACGAUUGGCAGCUAUCGCUGUGGCUGAAAGAGUUGCCGCAGAGAGACGGGAAAGGAUUGGUCAAACAAUUGGUUAUCAGAUCCGAUUAGAAAGCAGGGUUUCUCCAAAGACACUUCUGACAUUUUGUACUAAUGGGGUAUUGCUUCGUACAUUGAUGGCAGGAGAUAGUACGUUGUCGACUGUGACACAUGUUAUCGUGGAUGAAGUGCAUGAAAGGGAUCGAUUUAGUGAUUUUUUACUUACAAAGUUAAGAGAUUUGUUGCAAAAGCACCCAACUUUGAAACUAAUUCUUUCUAGUGCUGCCUUGGAUGUAAAUCUCUUUAUAAGAUAUUUUGGAAGUUGUCCAGUGAUAUAUAUACAGGGAAGACCAUUUGAAGUAAAAGAAAUGUUUCUGGAAGAUAUUUUAAGAACAACUGGAUAUACAAACAAAGAAAUGUUAAAAUAUAAAAAGGAAAAACAGCAAGAAGAGAAACAACAAACCACACUUACAGAAUGGUACUCAGCUCAAGAAAAUAGUUUCAAGCCUGAAUCUCAGAGGCAGAGAACUGUUCUAAAUGUGACUGAUGAGUAUGACUUACUGGAUGAUGGUGGUGAUGCUGUCUUCAGUCAGCUGACUGAAAAAGAUGUGAAUUGCCUUGAACCAUGGUUAAUAAAGGAAAUGGAUGCUUGCCUUUCUGAUAUAUGGCUACAUAAAGAUAUUGAUGCCUUUGCUCAGGUCUUUCAUCUCAUUUUAACUGAAAAUGUUAGUGUUGAUUACAGACAUAGUGAAACCAGUGCAACAGCUCUGAUGGUUGCUGCAGGACGUGGCUUUGCAAGUCAAGUAGAACAGUUAAUCAGUAUGGGAGCCAAUGUCCAUAGUAAAGCAUCAAAUGGCUGGAUGGCAUUGGAUUGGGCUAAACACUUUGGGCAGACUGAAAUUGUGGAUCUUCUAGAAUCUUACAGUGCUACACUGGAAUUUGGAAAUCUAGAUGAAAGUUCUCUGGUUCAAACAAAUGGAAGUGACCUCAGUGCUGAAGACAGAGAGCUCCUGAAAGCUUAUCAUCAUAGUUUCGAUGAUGAAAAAGUAGACUUGGAUUUGAUCAUGCAUCUUCUAUACAAUAUCUGCCAUAGUUGUGAUGCUGGUGCAGUACUAAUUUUUCUGCCUGGAUAUGACGAAAUUGUUGGACUGAGAGAUCGCAUCCUGUUUGAUGACAAGCGGUUUGCUGACAGUACACAUAGAUACCAAGUCUUUAUGCUUCAUUCAAAUAUGCAAACAUCCGAUCAAAAGAAAGUAUUAAAAAACCCACCUGCAGGUGUUCGAAAAAUAAUUCUUUCCACCAAUAUUGCUGAAACCAGCAUCACAGUCAAUGAUGUUGUCUUUGUUAUUGAUUCUGGUAAGGUGAAAGAGAAAUCCUUUGAUGCUCUGAAUUUUGUUACAAUGUUAAAAAUGGUAUGGAUUUCCAAAGCUAGUGCCAUACAGCGGAAAGGCAGGGCAGGGCGAUGUAGACCUGGAAUUUGUUUUCGUCUGUUCAGUAGACUCCGAUUCCAGAAUAUGUUGGAAUUUCAGACUCCGGAACUUUUGAGAAUGCCAUUACAGGAACUUUGCUUACAUACCAAGCUGUUAGCCCCAGUUAAUUGUCCCAUUGCUGAUUUUCUUAUGAAAGCUCCUGAACCUCCACCAGCUUUAAUUGUAAGAAAUGCUGUACAAAUGCUUAAGACAAUAGAUGCAAUGGAUACAUGGGAAGAUCUGACUGAACUUGGGUAUCAUUUGGCUGACUUGCCAGUAGAACCACAUCUUGGUAAAAUGGUCUUGUGUGCUGUUGUUUUAAAGUGUCUGGACCCCAUCCUUACAAUUGCUUGCACACUAGCUUAUCGAGAUCCUUUUGUACUACCUACUCAGGCCUCUCAAAAACGUGCAGCUAUGCUUUGUAGGAAACGUUUUACUGCAGGAGCUUUCAGUGACCAUAUGGCACUUCUCAGAGCAUUCCAGGCCUGGCAAAAAGCACGAAGUGAUGGGUGGGAGCGAGCCUUUUGUGAAAAGAAUUUUCUUUCACAGGCUACUAUGGAAAUAAUCAUAGGCAUGAGAACACAGUUGCUUGGUCAACUUAGAGCAUCAGGUUUUGUUAGAGCACGAGGUGGUGGUGACAUUCGGGACGUUAACACAAACUCUGAGAAUUGGGCUGUCGUUAAAGCUGCAUUGGUGGCAGGCAUGUAUCCUAAUUUAGUCCACGUGGACAGAGAGAAUCUAGUGUUGACAGGGCCAAAGGAGAAAAAAGUACGAUUUCAUCCUGCUUCAGUUCUCAGUCAGCCUCAAUAUAAAAAGAUUCCUCCAGCCAAUGGUCAAGCUGCAGCAAUUAAGGCACUGCCCACAGAUUGGCUUAUUUAUGAUGAAAUGACCAGAGCCCAUAGAAUAGCUAAUAUUAGAUGUUGUUCAGCAGUGACGCCUGUCACUAUAUUGGUAUUCUGUGGACCAGCUAGAUUGGCAAGUAAUGCUCUUCAGGAACCUUCAUCCUUUAGAGUGGAUGGCAUUCCCAAUGACAGUAGUGAUAGUGAAAUGGAGGACAAAACUACAGCUAAUUUGGCAGCCUUGAAACUUGAUGAGUGGCUCCAUUUCACACUGGAGCCAGAGGCAGCUAGUUUAUUGCUGCAGCUCAGACAGAAGUGGCAUAGCUUAUUUUUACGCCGAAUGAGAGCUCCAUCUAAACCUUGGUCUCAAGUUGAUGAAGCUACCAUAAGAGCAAUUAUAGCUGUUUUAAGCACUGAAGAACAGUCUGCAGGUUUACAACAACCAUCUGGGAUUGGCCAAAGGCCAAGGCCUAUGUCUUCAGAAGAGCUUCCUUUGGCCUCAUCUUGGAGGUCAAAUAAUAGUAGGAAAAGUUCAGCAGAUACUGAAUUUUCUGAUGAGUGUACUACUGCAGAAAGAGUACUGAUGAAAUCUCCAUCUCCAGCAUUACACCCACCUCAGAAGUACAAAGAUAGAGGAAUUUUACAUCCUAAACGAGGUACUGAGGACCGAUCAGAUCAGUCUUCUCUGAAAUCUACAGACAGCAGUAGUUACCCAAGUCCUUGUGCUAGUCCUUCUCCUCCAUCCUCAGGAAAGGGCUCAAAAUCUCCUUCGCCAAGACCAAACAUGCCUGUUCGAUACUUCAUAAUGAAGAGUAGCAAUUUGAGAAACCUUGAAAUUUCUCAACAGAAGGGUAUCUGGUCUACAACUCCUAGUAAUGAACGGAAGCUAAAUCGAGCCUUUUGGGAAAGCAGCAUAGUUUACUUGGUAUUUUCUGUUCAAGGAUCUGGACAUUUCCAGGGAUUUUCUAGGAUGUCUUCUGAGAUUGGAAGGGAAAAGAGUCAGGACUGGGGCUCUGCUGGACUAGGAGGAGUAUUUAAGGUGGAGUGGAUACGAAAAGAAAGCCUUCCCUUUCAAUUUGCACACCAUUUACUCAAUCCAUGGAAUGACAACAAGAAAGUGCAGAUAAGCAGGGAUGGGCAGGAACUAGAACCUCUGGUUGGUGAACAGUUGCUCCAGUUAUGGGAACGUCUUCCCUUGGGAGAAAAAAACACAACUGAUUGACACUCAGGUUAUACCAUCUUGACUUUGAGUAUUGGCAGUAUUUGUGAUCAUUAGGAACCUUUCAGAUUAUUUAUCUUUUUUUUUCCCCUUUCUUCUAGAACUCUUAGCUGUGGAAGAACAUCAUGCCUAUUUAUAACCACUGAAUGCACUGACUUUCAAAAACUGAGGUGGGGUGUGUGUUACGAAUGGGCUUUUUAACACUUUUAGAGUGUUGCUUUAGAACUACCAUCUUCAUAUACAGGAGAAAGGAAGCAUUUAAAUUUUUAUAGUGAUUAUAGAGAAUGAUUAUAUGAUGUUUGUAAUGAAUAAAAUAGUAGUUUCAUUAUUUGGCACAAUAGCAGUUUAUUUUAAACAAACAAUUUGAAGUUAAACAUUUCAUUUUUAAAAACACUGAAUUACAGUUCUUAUUGAUGACUUUUUAAUGCAGAGUAAGUUGUUUAAGAAAGGCCUGAAUAUAUCAGAACAUCUGAGCACCAUUUUAGAAGAGUCAACUCUUAAGAUUAUCAUUAGAAAACAAAUACGUCAACACCUAUGAAAAGAAGCGGGGAAAACAACAACAAGGACAACAACAAAAAACCAGUGAAAUUCUACAAGUGUCCCUUUUAAAAAUAGUGUGUGCUAACUAAGGGCUAUUCAUUCUGCCAUUUUUAACUUGAGACACAUUUAAGAAUAAAGUUGGAUGUUCUUUUUCUGUGAUUAUGAAAUGCAAUAAAAUCUGAAUAAAGGGCAAAGUUUCUUCCUGAUCAGAUUAGAUUAAGUGCUUAGUUUUAUUCCUAAUUCUGCCCCUUUUAACCUGAUGUGUACCUUACUCUUUCCUCCCUCUCUUCCUCCCUUCCUCCUCUCCCCGCUCCUUUCCUGCAUUUCUCCCUCCCUCCUUCCCUCGUCACAUCUCUUAUAUGAGCACAGUAAUUAUGACCUUUUUGUUUUGGCUACAACUUGAUUGAAACAAGUUCAAAAUUUAAACAAGUUCAUACAAGUUUUUAAAAAUUCUCAACUGGUAGCUUGCUUGCUGUGCGUCUUCCAAACUAAAGCCUGCAAGCGCCACAAUUCUAAGUGCCGCCUUCCAUUUUUUUUCAGUAUGUUUUCACUGGCUUAUGUUUUCAGAUAUGAUUUUCCUUUUUCGCAUAUAUGGUUUAAUAAAUGGGGGAUAAUUUUUUUUUUGUAAAUCCGUGCUUGUGCCAAGUCUCAUAUUUCUUUGCCAUCUCAGAAUUAUCUUUUUACCACCACUGUUUAUAAAAUUUCCUUAGAGACUUUUUGAAGGGAAAAUAGAGCAACAGGGAAAAAUGAAAGAAAUGUCUUGGUUACUGAGCUCUAAAUAGACAGGUUUGAUGGCACUUCUCAUGAUACAUUUUAGUUAUUCUUAUAAAAGCAAACAGGCAAACAUGAGUGUAAAUUAAAGACAAAAAGAAAACUCUGGUUUUAUAUUUGAGAACACGUGAAAAAUCAUGGGUCAACAUAAAAUCUUGAGAACCUUCUACUUUCUCUGGGAAAGCAUUAUAUAGUGGUGCAUUAGUUUAGAAAGUCAGCUAUGAUUUUGCCUAUAGUUCUAGUUAUUAGCUUUGGGGUUUUCUUGUACUUUAAGACAUACCUGUAAAUUGAACCUAUUUGAAUUAUAUUCCACUGUAUGUGUAUUAUGGCUCUUUUCCUAUUAGAGCAACUUGUGUUUCCCUGAUAAUGUGUACAUUUUUUAGGCAUGUACUUAAUAGUUCACAAUGUUCUAAAUUUGGAAGGACUUAAAAAAAAAACUUGUUUAAAUUUCCAUCUGUUUUGUAAUAUCUAGCUCUAUAUGUAAAUGAUGGGUUUGUUGGUAUUUAAAAUGAAUACAACUUGAAUGUAAUUAAAGUGCUGUUUUUUGGAAGCGAUAAACUUUAAAUAUACUUAUUAAAAUGAAAUUCUAUUAA